GCAGCUCCCCGGACCCGCAGCCAUGGCCGACAUCAAGACGGGCAUCUUCGCCAAGAACGUCCAGAAGCGACUCAACCGCGCGCAGGAAAAGGUCCUCCAAAAGCUGGGGAAAGCUGAUGAGACAAAAGACGAACAGUUCGAAGAAUAUGUCCAGAACUUCAAACGGCAAGAAGCAGAGGGUACCAGACUUCAGCGAGAACUCCGAGGAUAUUUAGCAGCAAUCAAAGGCAUGCAGGAGGCCUCCAUGAAGCUCACAGAGUCGCUGCAUGAAGUCUAUGAGCCUGACUGGUAUGGGCGGGAAGAUGUGAAAAUGGUUGGUGAGAAAUGUGAUGUGCUGUGGGAAGACUUCCAUCAAAAACUCGUGGAUGGGUCCUUGCUAACACUGGAUACCUACCUGGGGCAAUUUCCUGACAUAAAGAAUCGCAUCGCCAAGCGCAGCAGGAAGCUAGUGGACUAUGACAGUGCCCGCCACCAUCUGGAAGCUCUGCAGAGCUCCAAGAGGAAGGAUGAGAGUCGAAUCUCUAAGGCAGAAGAAGAAUUUCAGAAAGCACAGAAAGUGUUUGAAGAGUUUAACGUUGACUUACAAGAAGAGUUACCAUCAUUAUGGUCAAGACGAGUUGGAUUUUAUGUUAAUACUUUCAAAAACGUCUCCAGCCUUGAAGCCAAGUUUCAUAAGGAAAUUGCGGUGCUUUGCCACAAACUGUAUGAAGUGAUGACAAAACUGGGUGACCAGCACGCCGACAAGGCCUUCACCAUCCAAGGAGCGCCCAGUGAUUCGGGUCCUCUCCGCAUUGCAAAGACACCAUCACCGCCUGAGGAGCCUUCACCCCUCCCGAGCCCGACAGCAAGUCCAAAUCAUACAUUAGCACCUGCGUCUCCCGCACCAGCACGGCCUCGGUCACCUUCACAGACAAGGAAAGGGCCUCCUGUCCCACCUCUACCUAAAGUCACCCCGACAAAGGAACUGCAGCAGGAGAACAUCAUCAGUUUCUUUGAGGACAACUUUGUUCCAGAAAUCAGUGUGACAACACCUUCCCAGAAUGAAGUCCCUGAGGUGAAGAAAGAGGAGACUUUGCUGGAUCUGGACUUUGAUCCUUUCAAGCCCGAGGUGACACCUGCAGGUUCUGCUGGAGUGACCCACUCACCCAUGUCUCAGACAUUGCCCUGGGACCUAUGGACGACUGACUCUUCAGAAAGUCUUUCCUUGUGUAACCUGAUCAUGGAGGAAACUCCAGACAGUGGGUUGGCCGAAGAAAUUCAAAGAUCUCAAAAUGAUAUAGGUGCAUUUACUUGGGGCCCUGACGCUAGUACAGACAGGGUCAGCCAAGAAGUUACCUCAGGUGGGUUUGGAGAAGACUCUGCAUGUCCCUCCGAAACAGAGCAAGACAUAAGAUUAUCCACCAGCCUGCUUUCGUCUGCUGACUGGCCCACUGUAGCUGAAGAGAGUGAGCAUGCCCCGGGGCCAGCCUUUCCAGGUGGAAAUGAACAACUGCCCCCAAAGCCUGCGCCGGAGGCUGGAGUUGCCAUUGCUGCUUGUGUGGAGAUGGAGCAGCUGUAUGACCCACUUGACUCAGACAUGCCAGCCAUGGACACAGCUGGCCUGUUCAAAGAAAGUCAUGAAGAUAUGAAGAAGUCAGAUGAAGAGGAAGAGAAACAGAAGAUGGAAGAUUCUCUGUGGGCAGGUGUGGAGGCGUGUCAAAAGGUAGACACUGGAGCUAUUGAUAUCAAGACACUAGAAGGUACAGAGGAAUUUGAAGAGAAAGCAUGUGAAAGGACAGGAAACAGAGUGGUAGAACUUCUUAAUACCAUAGGAAAGGAAGACCAUAAGACCUUAAAAAUUAAUGAAGUGGAAACUAGAAAAGAUCUAAGAGCAGGGUAUAAGGAAAGUACAAACGCCAAUGAAAAUUAUUUUGAGAAAACUGACCUAUUAGAAAAGGACAUGGAAGGAGGAGAUAUGGCAAAAGAACUUAGUGACAGAGACCAAGGUCUACAUGAUGGAAUUCAAAAGGUAAUCAAUAAUUGUGGAAUGAUAGAAGGCUUUGGAGCCAAACCUGCCAAUCACCCAGAUAUCUUGAAUCCAUCUCUCCAGACCUACUCUGUAUCUAAUAUUGAAGAUGGCAGCCCUGAGGGAUGGGAUUUGACUAGAAAAGACAUAAAGAAAAAUGCAAUAGACACUCCCAACCAUGAUAUGAUAUUUUACCCAGCACAAGACAGUACAGAUGCUGAAGAAAUUCAGUGUGAGACUGUGUUAAAUGCUCUUGUAGGUGACAGGGAUAAAAAUCAGGCUGUUUUAUCAAUAAAACUUGAAGUAGAAGCUCAGUCUAGGACUGACCUUAAUUAUUCUCUGGGAAGAGAUGCAAACAGAAGAGAUUUAUGUUCAUGUAAGGCAGAAAGUUCACUAAUAGAAGGGUCUGAAAGAACAGUAACUGAGAACCGUAGUCAUACUGUUAACUUGCCAAGAAUUGCAGAGAUAGACUCUUGGGGAACAGAUCCAGGUCAAAUCUGGCAGCCAAGCUUGGAUUCAGCAAUGAAUAAUUUGGAUAUAACAGGAUUCUCUGGUAUACCAGAUGGCCAAGCAAGUGGAUUUGCCAGUUGUCUGGAUUCUAUUAACCACUGGCCUAUCAGAGAUACAGAAGGCUUAGAUAAUAGCUGGACACAUUCAGAUGUAGUUGAGCACAAGGAAGAACUGAAGGUGGACUUACUAGCAGGUGAUUGUAGGGAACAAGCCAUUGCUAGCUGCUGGGAACAAAGCCAGGAGAUAGCAAGACCAUUGAUUUUGGGGACCUCCUGGAAUGCUAGCACUGAGAGUUCUGCUAGUUCCCGAGACCAGGACAUCAACAACUCAGAUUUAUCUGAAGAUGAAAUUGCUAACCAGAGAUAUGGAUUGUUGUACCAAGAAAUAGAGGCUGACAAAGACGAGGCUUCUGGUGGUUCAUUUAAUGGAUUCACACAGCCCCAGGAUACUUCAUUAUUCACAAUGCAGACAGACCAGAGUAUGAUCUGCAACUUGGCUGAAUCUGAACAGGCUCCACCCACAGAGCCAAAAGCAGAGGAGCCUCUGGCUGCUGUCACACCUGCCGUUGGUCUGGACCUUGGAAUGGACACUCGGGCUGAGGAGCCAGUGGAGGAGGCAGUGAUCAUACCUGGAGCUGAUGCUGAUGCAGCUGUUGGAACCUUGGUGUCAGCAGCUGAGGGGGCCCCAGGAGAGGAAGCAGAGGCGGAGAAGGCCACUGUCCCUGCCGGGGAAGGAGUAAGUUUAGAGGAGGCCAAAAUUGGAACUGAAACCACUGAGGGUGCAGAGAGUGCCCAACCUGAAGCAGAGGAGCUCGAAGCAACAGUGCCUCAGGAGAAGGUCAUUCCUUCGGUGGUCAUAGAGCCUGCCUCCAACCAUGAAGAGGAAGGAGAAAACGAAAUAACUAUAGGUGCAGAGCCCAAGGAGACCACCGAGGACGCGGCUCCUCCGGGCCCCACCAGCGAGACACCGGAGCUGGCUACGGAGCAGAAGCCUAUCCAGGACCCUCAGCCCACGCCUUCUGCACCAGCCAUGGGGGCUGCUGACCAGCUAGCAUCUGCAAGGGAGGCCUCUCAGGAAUUGCCUCCUGGCUUUCUCUACAAGGUGGAAACACUGCAUGAUUUUGAGGCAGCAAAUUCUGAUGAACUUACCUUACAAAGGGGUGAUGUGGUGCUGGUGGUCCCCUCAGAUUCAGAAGCUGAUCAGGAUGCAGGCUGGCUGGUGGGAGUGAAGGAAUCAGACUGGCUUCAGUACAGAGACCUUGCCACCUACAAAGGCCUCUUUCCAGAGAACUUCACCCGACGCUUAGAUUAGGGCAACAAGUACUGCAAGAAGGAGCUCAGUUACGGGGUUUUUAAACCUUCAUGAAAACCUGAAGAGUUCACUUUUGUUAUUAUGCUCUUAAUGAUUUACAGACUGAUGCCAGACAAACCUUGGGAAGAUGUAUCAAUGGAGCAUGUGUGCAAAAAAAUGUAAGAGGAAAAAAAGUAAAUUAAGGAAAAAAUCCUCACUCAUUCCCAUGUUGUCAAUAACAGGUUUGUUUGUGCUUUGUCCAAGCUGUGGAGACUCUUGUACUUGAUCCCCUCCCACCAAUUCUAAAGUAGCUUUCUCCAGAUCAGACUUUAAUUUCUCUGCAUCAGGUGUAUCGUAUUGAGUGGCUGCCCUGCAGAAGAUGUGAUGAAUUAUCCUGUAGUACAAGAUUAUCUUAUUCCCCUGCCCAGGUGUGAGCACGUGCUCUCGCUCCCUUUCAGGUUUACUAUGUUUAAAACUAAACUGCUGCAAAAGUUCUCAAUGUUCUUUUCCAACACAUCUAUAUAUAUAUGGACACACAGUCACGCAAGCUAGUUCCCAUGACUCCUGGAUCUAUGUGUAUGCAGAAGGCUACAUAUACAUAGUUGCUUCUUUCCUUUCCAUUGUAGCUCUUUGCCUCUCAAUUGUCAUUGAUACAUGCAUUGCUCUUAUUCUGUCUGGCAUUACAAUUGCAGUUUUGCCUAAUGGCAAAACCAGCCAUCCCAUUGGCAAAAGAGUCAACAGUAUCUGUGUUUGUACUGUGCAGUUUUCAGGAUGAGAUGACAGAUAGCACGACUACACUGAGGCACCCUCAGAGAAGGCAGGGCCUGAUUUAUCUAGCUGUCCAGCCGCUGUGGCUGGAGGUAGGCUAGUUGGGAUGGGCAGCUAAGCAGUCUUCUCUUCUGCCUUUAUGAGAUUGGGUAGAAAGAUGGGGCAUAUUCAUCUACCCCCAAAAGAACACUAUAAAAACAGCUCCUCUAUAUUUCCACCUCUUUCUAUUUAUGCAACUCAUCUUCACAGAUUGUUCUAAAGUAAAAUAGAUGGUGUAUGCUGUAUCCACAAAUCAUCUGUAACAAUUAUGUUUUCAGUGCUGUGUCAUUCCAAAUAAACCUUUGGUAAUCUUCAACGAUUACCCUAA